AGAUCGGCUUUCAGCUGCAGCCUCCGGGCCGGCCGGGAAGGCGGGGAGCGGGCGGCGGCGGCGGAGGAGGGGGAGGCGGCGGCGGCUGCAGCAUCCAGAGCUGGCCGUGGCGGCCGGCGCGCCCCGCGCACAAAAGCACCCAGCCCCAGGGGAGGGCGAUGAACACACCACAUCCCGGGCCCGGGCCCCAGCUGCUGCUACCGCUGCGUGCGCUCAGGGCGCUGGGGAAGACGCCCGGCGCGCCGGGGGCCAGCGGCCGAGGCGCGGCCCGUGCGCCCUGAGCGCGGGACUCGUCGCCCUCCGGGUCAGGCGCCAAGCUUCCAAGCGGCUAGAGCGCGGGCCUUGGAGCGCCCCCAGGAUCGCUUCAGUAAGGCGCUUCCCCACUCCAGGCCCGACCCCCGGCGCCUGAGCGCCAACUUCGCCAAGAACGCUCCUAACUCCAGGCCAUCCUGCAGCGCAGAGGGGGCGCUGCUGCCGGGCAUCAGCCGUGAGGACGCGCCCCUGGCCGUGCGGAGAGAGCCGGCAUUUGCGGGUCACUCGGGCGCCCCUGAGUGGGCGGCGGCGGCAGCAGACCCCUCUCCAGGGAGUCCAGGACCUGCCAGCGCUGGGGAUUCUUCCCGAACAGGCGCUUGCCCUCUCUUUUAUGGAGCUUGGGCCCCUGCCGCAGCCCGGUAGAGGCUGUGGAGGUCUACCGUCCGGAAGCCUGGUUCCCAGCCCCGUGGCCCAUUCCUGGCUACGGGGAGUGGAGGCUCCCACGAGGUAGCGGUGGCCUGCAGCGGCCUCCUCCCCGCAGUGAAGCAUGGGCCAGAAGCUCUCGGGGAGCCUCAAGUCAGUGGAGGUGCGAGAGCCGGCGCUGCGGCCGGCCAAGCGGGAGCUGCGGGGUGCAGAGCCCGGGCGGCCGGCGCGGCUGGACCAGCUGUUGGACAUGCCAGCGGCGGGGCUGGCUGUGCAGCUGCGGCACGCGUGGAACCCCGAGGACCGCUCGCUCAACGUCUUCGUCAAGGACGACGACCGGCUCACCUUCCACCGGCACCCCGUGGCCCAGAGCACCGACGGCAUCCGCGGCAAGGUGGGCCACGCCCGCGGCCUGCACGCCUGGCAGAUCAACUGGCCGGCUCGGCAGCGCGGCACCCACGCUGUAGUUGGUGUGGCCACGGCCCGUGCUCCCCUGCACUCCGUGGGCUACACGGCGCUGGUAGGCAGUGACGCCGAGUCGUGGGGCUGGGACCUGGGCCGCAGCCGCCUCUACCACGACGGCAAGAACCAGCCCGGCGUGGCCUACCCGGCCUUUCUGGGGCCCGACGAGGCCUUUGCGCUGCCCGACUCGCUGCUCGUGGUGCUGGACAUGGAUGAGGGCACACUCAGCUUCAUCGUGGAUGGCCAGUACCUGGGCGUGGCCUUCCGAGGUCUCAAGGGCAAGAAGCUGUACCCGGUGGUGAGUGCCGUGUGGGGCCACUGUGAAGUCACCAUGCGCUACAUCAACGGCCUUGACCAAAACUGAAUUCCAGGCUUUUUAAGAAAGCAUAGAGUUCCCUGGGUCUACUAAGAACCAUCUGGCAGUCCAGCCAAGAAAAGGGGCCUCUGUAAAGCAGUGAACUCAGCGUGAGCUUUGGUAAGUCUCAACUCUGUCCUGUUCUUGGGCAGGGCAUUUGUGUUUCAGUCUUCCCUACCUGGGGCAAGUGAGUGACCCAGGGCUUGGAGCCCACCCCGACCUCUGUAGCUGUGACAUAUGUCCCCCGCCUUGUCCAUCAUGCUGCAGCCUCUCCACAUUCUUGGCUGGACCCUGGGAAGGGCAGCACCAGGGCAGGGCUCUGCUUGGGUAAGCUCUGGCUUCCCCUUUUGUCACCUGGGGUGGUGGAGCUCAAGCUGGCCUGGGCCCUUGUCACCACCAUGCUGCGCAAGCCACCCAGGAGAGAAGUGGUGAAUUGUGGGCUUGUAUUUCCUUUUUGGCUGACACAGGCAACCUCCCUUGGAUAUUUAAGGUGUUCUGCCACAGUGGACUGUUCAGAUAUGUGAAAGUUAAAAAAGCAUACUCAACCUGAACUGAGUUGUACCCAGAGUCUGGUGUGGGAUUAUAAAAGGCAGGAGGCGGACAGGUCCUGGAAAGAGCACUUGUCUGGGAGCCAGGAAACCUGGCCCAGUGGGCUCCAGCUUGCCCACUUGCUCUGUGACCUCGGGGAAGUCAGCUCCUCUCUUUGUGCCUCAGUUUCUCCACUGCAAGGAGGGGAUUGGAUAAGAUGACCUCAAGUGGUCUCCAUCAUUCUGCAGUCUCUGAGAUGGAGGGACUGGGCAUCUGGAUUUUUUGGAUGACAAACACUUUACACUGUGGUGCUACAUCAGCUCCACAUCUGCCCUAUCCAAUGUGGGAGCCACUAGCCCUAACCAUAUGUGGUCGUUUAAUUAAAAUCAAAUAAAGUUAAAUGUUCAGUUACUUGGUUGUGCUAGCCGCAUCCAAAUGCUCCACAGACACGGCUCGUGGCUGCCCUAUUGGAUGAGCCCAUGUAAACCAUUCCGACCGCGGCUCAAAGUUCUACUGGAUGGGGCUGCUUUAGAGCCACUGGAGAGGGCUGAGGAGCCCCAGAGAGAGAGCACAGGCCUCUGUUUCUGCCAUGGGACUUCUUCUGGGCCAGUGGUCAGCAGAGUGGCUCCAGGGCCCAGGGAGUGAGUUCAAGUGGGGGUGGGGGUAGGAGAAAGAUUUAGCCCAGAUACCAGCCAAUGAGUGUCAGGCUGCAGGACCAGAAAACCUUAGGCGAAUGUCAAAGGUCUUUGGUGGUGGGGGGUAGCCACUGACAGGAGGUAUGCCAGGAAUGCUGAGGAGGGCCUGGGGGACAGCAGGGGCCAGGAGCUCUGCGGGGGGAGGGGCAGCUGUGCAGAACACAGUGGCAGUUCUGCAGCAGGCCUCUUGCUAGCUCUGUGUCCUUGGGGACGUCCCUGAGCCUGCUGAGCCUCCAUUUCUUUGUGGGUGAAAUGGGAAAAAUAAGAAAGAGGGCUGUUAUGGAGAUGAAAUAAAGCAAAACCUGUGAAAGCCCCUUGUAAAUCGCAAAGGCCUGGACGGCGUUAGGGGCUACUUCAUAUGGCACUAUUAUUUAUCUCAGCUUGUAAUCCUAGACUGUCCUCAGUUAUGAUUUUAAGGUUCUGGGGUGUCCAUCCUGUCUUUCUGAUGGGGCUGUAGACCAUUUAGAGAAGGAGACCAGCCAUGUCCCUCCUGUAUCCCCAACAGCCAUGAACAGUGCUGGUGGCUGCCGCAUGGGGAGCACACGUCUUUCUCUUUUCCUCCUGACCUGGUGGCCUUUCACCAGGCCAUAUUCCUGCCCCAAGAGUUGUUGAACACAUUCCUUGUCCCUGACACAUGUGUGCAUCUGGCUGGGUCUGGUUGUCAUUUGCUGAACCCAUGGCCCAUCGUGAGCCCCACCACAUGAAAACAAUUCGGGGGCAGAGGUCAAAAGCCAGAGCUGGGCUUUGCCAGGUCUCCCAGGGAGUGCGCCUGGCAGGAGGUAGCCCAGUGCCAGGCUGCAUCAGGCGGCCCCUCCCCAGGCUGGGCCAGGCUCUCAUCUGCAUCCAUGGUUGGGAGGUGGCAUUUCUGGCUGACUUAUUGAUGAUGGAUUGUCUGCUACACUCUAGCCCUGGGUGGGUUCAUUGCUUAGGUCUGGCUUUGGCUUUUCGUGAGGUCCACACCACAGACAUGCAGAACACAGAGAGGAGUUUGAGCCCUGCCAGAUAAACUUUUUCUGUCACAGAACUGCUGUGCUUUCCAGCAAUAUAGGCGGUGAAGAAAAGCCAAAGUAACCAUUUGAUGAUUAUCUCCUUGCCCCAACCCAGGUGCUAUCUAUCUAUCUAUCUAUCUAUCUAUCUAUCUAUCUAUCUAUCUUUCCAUUAAAUCCUUUUAGCCCCAUGUGUGAAGUGUUAAUAAUAUCCCCAUUUCACAGAUGGGGAAACUGAGGCUGUGAACGGCUGAAAGGUUUCAGGGCCAGAACUAGAAUUUGGACUCUAGUCUGCCUGAUUUCAGGCUCAAAGCGUCCCUUUCAGAAUGUCCUGAGGGCUCUUUUCUUCCCCUGCUGUCUUCACUCUGACCAUGAUGAGCUGCACCAGGCUUUCUAAAUAUCUGAAACGCUCUACGCCAUCCCUGCUUUCUUUGUUUGGCCUCAGCGUGGUGAUCUGGGCUUCCUCAGAUUUGGGUUUAAGGCCAGGUUUUGCUGAGCUGUGUGACCUGUGUCCACCAUGGACCUCCCCAGACCAUGAUGAGCUGCACCAGGCUUUCUAAGUAUCUGAAAUGCUCUAGGCCAUCUCUGCUUUCUUUCUUUGGCCUCAACGUGGUGAUCUGGGCUUCCUUAGAUUUGGGUUUAAGGCCAGGUUUUGCUGAGCUGUGUGACCUGUGUCCACCACAGGUCCCCCCAGGUGCCCUCACUAGAGUGGGGGUGCCUGGCCAGCUUAUUUGAUGGAGGAGAUAGAGGGCUAGAGUGCCACGUGCAUGGCUUCCCCGGCUGGUUUGGAGGGCCCAUGGGGACUGUGUACUGUGACUUUUCCAAGGAGACAAUCACUGUUGUCUCCACACUGCCACCCCCCCACCCUCUGUAGAGCCCUGGAUGGUGCCCCUUAUGGUCCCAGGGCGUGUCCAGCAGAAGAUAUGAGAAAGGCCCCUGCCCCACUUGGGGCUUAGCUCUGCCCCUUUCUCUGGGCAGGGCCAGGGAGGUGACCCUUUUGUGUGGCACCCAGCACCAGAACCUGCUUCUCCACCUCCCCCAGCAGAGGAGUGCGACCUCCCAGCCCUCAGUGCAGCCUCCACAUCCCCCGGCGGGCAAGUCUCUGCCUCCAUGCUUCUGCUUGUGCUGUGCUCCCUGCCUGAUGCUGGCCCACUUCUCCACCUGUCUAAAGCUAUCCUUUCUGGAGGCUCCGAGCAAUGCCACCUUGGUUUCUAAAGUCCUCUUUAAUGACCUUAGUCCAUAUUGCCCAUUCUGUUCUGUGCUGCUGGAGCACAUUUGCGGUGGUGAAGGGGGUCUGUGGGGUCUUUAUAAGGCAUGGCCCCUUCUUAGUGAGCAAUCCUCACAGGCCUUUUUCUGAGACUCCUCGUUUGACUCUGGCCCCUGCUUACCUCCCUCCCCUCUGAACUCCAGAACCCUCUGGAGGCCCUGCAGGGUAGAGGGGAAAGACUCUGAAGUUGGGCAGAAAGCCUGGGCUUGCCUCACAGCUCUGCCACUGCAGGCUGUGGGACUCUGCUCUUUGGCGUCAUCAUCUGUAGAAUGCGGCUAAUAAUGGCAGAGCGAGGUGGAUGAGGCCGCAGUGUGGGAAGCCCGGCGUCGCUGGGUAGAGCUCAUGUGGAUUUACUUCCUCUCCCAGAGAGUAACAGCAUCUGAUGCAGACCCAGGGAGACAGUAGGCACACGAUAAAUACUUCUUGACUUUUUUAAUGCUUUCUUUUGUGAUGUUUCUUUUAAAAGCAACCUAAGGCACUCUAUGGCCUGGAGCAGAAGCAUAGGGCUUGCUCAGCCUCUGAAGGGGCCUCUAACCGUCCCUUCCCUCCACCUCCCCCACACCCCUCUCCUGGCCUCUCCUUGCCCUCACCCUCAUGCCGCCUGGGUGGCUGCACUGGCCUAUAAAUCAAACGGGUCCCUGGAGACCUUUGACCCAAACCAGAUGGCUGUACUAUGCCAGCACAGAGUAAGCUUAGCUUCCAACAAUGCUUGGCCCCCCUCCCCCUGCCUGCCCUGGGGCUUGGAACAUUUUUAGGCAGCUGCCCUGUCAAUCACAAACACUUGGUGAUCCCAGCCCGGGCAGCAGCUGGAGGCUGUGACCUCUCCAAGACUUCAGGGACCAUCUUGGAGAUAUUCCAUUAAGCCAUAUAAAGAUCUCUGGAGGGUCUGUGGUGUCUACUUGUUAUGGCACAGGCAUUAACCUGGACCAAUAGACCAAGCUGGCAUUCCCUGUGCUGCUAUCUCUCCCUCCUCCUCCUCCAAGAAGCUUUUCUGCACUACGGCAGCUGCUGGAGCUUCUAUAGCUCAGAAUGUCUGACCCCUCCAGAUGCUCAUUCAUACCUUGUUCAUUCUUUCUGCAAACAUUUACUGUGCUUCAUCUGCCUGGGCCCAUGGGGAAGAUCAGACACUGCCCUUGUGCCAGUAAGUCCGAAAGACAGCUAUGGAUACAGAAUUGUAGGAAUUGGUGAUAGGGGUUGUAAUUGAGCAGGAAGGCCAGGGCACUGUGGGAACUCAAGAUGGAUGCACUGCAGUGUCAGAAUCCAGGACAGCUUUCCAGAGAGGAGUGCUUGAGCCGAGUCUUGGAGGAUGGGUUGGCAUUUGCCAAAUAGAUAGGGUGGCAGAAGGGUGCUUCAGAUAGAAGGAAUAGCAUGUGGAAGGAAGGUACAGGCACAGGAUGGGAACCAGCUUGAUGGAUUCAGGGACCUGCAAGUUGGACAGCAUGCUGGAAGUACACCUAGGGGAGAAAAUGAGGAGUUGGAACUGUAUCAGUGAGAAUUAGAUCUGCUUGUUUGCAACCAAAAAUGCCUAAUACUAUGGGCUUAAACAAGAAUUUCUCUCUCAUGGAAGAGAAGUCUGGAAGCAGGCAGUGCAAGGAUGUUGUGGGGCUCCAUGAUCACUGCCCCAGGCUCCUUCUGCCUGCUGCUCCACCUUCCUACCUUGUGGCUUCCAUUCCCAUAGGUACCUCAUUGUCUGGAAUGGCUGCUAGAGCUUCAGCCAUUGCACCCACAUUCCAGGCAGCAGAAUGGAAGAGCUAAAGGAGGGCACGUGACUCAUCUUUUAAAAGAUUUUUCUGAAAUGCCUUACUAUGCUUCUGUGCAUAGCCCAAUGGCCAGAACACUAUCACAUGACCACUUCUAGUGCAAGGAAGCUGAGAGAUACAGUUCUGAUCAGUAGGUGCUGCCUAGAGCACUGUUCUGCAAAGGAUUCUGCAGCCCAAUCUUACGUCUGUGGGAAAGAACACUGUGAUCAAUUAAUGAUGCCUCCCUUUGGUGUGGGUGUGGAGCCAAUAGCAUGUGUCUUGCUGGUCUUCUGCCAGAAGGUCCCCUCCCUAGGGAUUCCCAAGGUUUGGUGCAGCUCCUGCAAACAGAGCUGGCACAUGGCCAGCCAUCCCCCAAAGCCCCAAAGCAGAGCGGAAUUUAGGUGAAGGGUUUCUUGGUGCUCUGCAGUCUGAUUUUAUUUCUGAUCUGCAGCCUCCUUAAGGCAUCCAUUGCCCUUCAGCAGGGCUUGAGUCUGCAGAAUGGUCUGUGUGGUUGGAGCAUGAAUUAGGAGGAAAGAAGGAAAUACAAUGUCACUAAUGUAGCUGCAGCCUCAUCCCCUGGUGAGAGGUUUUCCAAAAUGCAGUAAUACAGAAAGAAUUUAAGGGAAGUUCUGAGCCAUUUUAUUUUCACACCUGGAAAUGCAUUGUCUUUUGGUUUAAUUUCACUCCUGCUGUGUGUCACAGCCCAGGGUUUCCUUAGCUGUGAAAGGGGGUAAUACUACCUUCCUUGAAGGGUUUUUGAGAGGAUCACAUGAAAUAAAAGAGGGCAAAGCAGGUGGGAGACACAGAGGGUAGCAAUUAGGUGCAGAGUUUAUGUUCAAACUGCCUGGGUUCCAGUCUUAGCUUUCCUGCUUGCUUGCUGUGUGAUCCUGCAUCUGUUAAUUAACCUCUCUGUGCUUCAGUUUCCUUGCCUGUAAAAUGGAGAUGAUGAUAAUAGUGCCCACCUUAUGGGGCUGUUUUGAGGCCUGUACAUAUGACAUAUACAUAAACAUCUUAAGACCUGGCACACAGUGUGGACGUGUAAGUGGUAAUGGCUCUUUGGCCAUGGUACAGUAUUUGGAUCCAACAGGUCUGGGAUAAGAUCCAGGGUAAAUUACUCUUCUAAGCCCCAGUUUCUUUAUUUGAAACAAGGAUAAUGUGACUUGCCUUGCAGAGUGAGGAUUACUGACAGAAUAACUGUAAAGUCCUGACACAUAGGACAUACGCAAUAAGUUAGAACUAUGGUGAAGAUUAUAAAAUGAUACCGUGUCCCAGGCUCUGUUAUCAGCACUUUAUAUGUGUCACCUCUUUUAUCUCAUAAGAACACUAUAGAGGCAGGUGGUGUUAACAUUCCUCUUGGGGAAACUGAGGCAUAGAGGCUUGCCCAAGGUCACGUAGCUGGUAAGAAAGGAAGCUGAGAGUUGAUCUCCUGGGUCAGCUGAUCCAGAGCCUGUGCUAUCCUGCUUGGGAACACUGAUUCUGCAGAGGAGCAGGCCCUGCGUUUAAGAGCAGAGGGAAGGGGAUAAAGGUGGCCCAGAGCUUCAGGGCCAGCUGCCUGGAAGAUGACACGCGCACAGCACAGAGGACUAGGGCUUCUGAGCCUUCACAGCCAGAUUUGCAUGCAGGACCCCGACCCUUAUUCAGGAGGAUGAGCUCUCUGAGCCUAUCUUGAAGGGGGCUGUCCUUCUGGGGCUGGCGUAGCAGGCAGUGUGCACAGUAGUAUGGCUGCAGUAGGUUGACUGGCCGGAAGGAGACCUCUAGGAGGCCUGGAGCAUGAGGCUGCAGAAUUUAGACUUCCUGUAGGCAGUGGGAGCUGUGUGACAGUCUGACGGAGCAUGAUGAAAGCCAGGUGUUAGGAGGAUUCUCCUUUAGUGAAGUGGUAGGAAGCACCAGGGGGCCUUGGACAGACAAAAUUGAAGAAGGUGGAGGGAGGCAGGCCACAUAGGGAGGUAACCCAGGAAGAGGGUCCCAGUAUGGGGUAAAAUGUCCAGCAUGUGCUGGGGGAGCCCCCAGUUGUAGGGUCCCAGUGACGUCAGGCACUGUGGCAGCUGCUUUACAUCCAUGAUCUCAUUUGAUCCUUAAAUAGUCCUGGGAAGUGUGUGUGAUGUACCCAUUUUCCAGAUGAGCAAACAGCCUCGGAAGGUCAAGUGGUGGCUUGAGGUUGCAAGGCCAGGGAGUGGCAGAGCUGGACCAGGGCCCAGGGCUGCAUACCAAGCCACAGAGUCCUGCAUUCCCCACGUGCCCACCAAGGCAAAUGCGGGCAGGGCAGAGGAGGAAUGGGAGGGGAUGAUGGCAAUUGUCUCUAGUCGCCUGUGAGGAGUUGCUGCCGGAUGCGUUCUGGCCUUGUCUGUGGUAGGGGUGGGGAGUGGUGAGAUGCUUCUGUACUUUACAACCUUAAAUGAUAGACUUUUCUUUAGGAAACAAAAGUUUGGUUGGGCUCAGUGAGCAGGAAAAUGGAAGUGACCCUUGAGCGGAGAUUUAAAGCCCUGUUGGCCAUUUAGGCAGCACUGUGUUUAACAGCUGAGACACAGCAUCAGGGUGAUAACUCCGCAGUGUGCUGUGGGGUGGGGAAUGGCCCAAGGGGGUCUCUCUGCUCUCUGAGUUCCAUCUGGUCCUGAAACUCCGUCCCCCAGGGCUCUCUUGGAAAUGGACCCAGGAGCUACCCACACCUUCCCCUGGACUGCAGAAGCUGUUAGUGCUGGCUUCAAGGGAAGUUGUUGCCAGCGGUACACAGGGACACAGAAAAGGGCGCACAGUUAAAUGUACUGCGUACAUCCAUGCUACAAAGAAUAAUGCUGGAAGGUAUAUUCCAAACAGGCUAUUGACGAUUACUUCUAGGUGGCAGGAUAAGACGUGAAUUUUCCUGCGUCUUUGCGCUUUUAUGUACUUCCAAAUCAACACAUACAAAAGGAUAUAACUGUGAAAAUUCUAAAGUGCCUCUAUCCCCACUUCCUAGCAGACUCUUGGGGUGCCCCCACCACAUCCUCUCAGCUCAACUGGUUAGGUACUGCUGUGGGCAUCAGUCAGUUUUGCUUUCUCCUAAGCUGCAGGUAGCCACUCAGCCGGAUGCAGGCAGCACCGGGAUGUGCAGGGGAGUUAACACCCUUGGGGAUACCCCUCAAUGACUCGGAGACAGGAGUCCAUGGUUAAGUGCCCCCAGCUCCCCAGCCUCCAGGGAGACAGUUCUGAGGUCCAUCCUACAUAGAUGCUCAGAGCAUCCUAGUGAAUGAGCCCAGGAUGCCCACAGCAGUAUGCAGCUCAUUCACACAUUCUCUCUACUCUUCCUCCCUUCCCUGUCUCACUUUCUCCGUCUCUCAUUUUCAUCUCCUGAGAUCCUCCCACAAAGCUAUCUGCACCCACAUCUUUGUCUCAGGAACCCAAACCAAGGCCCAAUCUGACCAAUUUCUCAUAGAGCUCCACAGAUAUAUUCUAGGCAUAUAUAAGCACAUCUGUGUCCAUAUCCAAACACUGAUAUAUACACUUUCUUUUUCACAGAGUACAAACGGGGCCACACUGAACUUACCAGUGUGCAACUCGCUUCCUUCAUGAUUGAAUGAAACAUUGCAGGAGGAAUUUCAGGCCAAGGAGCCCUUCCUGGCAGCGUCAAUCCUGCUUAGGGGGUCAUCCCCAUCCUCCAAGUUUGGGACCAACCCAAGCCAGAGGCUACUGGUCCUUAAGGAAGGGGUGUGUGUGACAAGUUUUUGCUCUCUUCAGGUGGACGAGGGUCCAAACACUGGCUGACCUUUCCCCAUCUGCACCGGGAGGCCAGACCAGGAUGGGGAUUUGCAGCCACAAAGAUUGGCCAAAACGGUUCCAGCCCAUACGUCCAGCAGGAGUAGAACAGUGCAGUAAGGACCCCAGGUGCCCACAGACCUCAGAAAGGAUACACAGGACACAGAGGAGUCAGGGAGUGAAAGGAGGGCUGUGCAGAGGAGGUAACACUCUGAGUCCUGAAAUCUGGGUAUUUGCCUAGUGGAGUAGAGCCUGGAGGAGAAGGAGGGGCCUAGCAGGAAGGCAAGGCAGGCCAGAGGCCAGCUUGAACAAAGGUGGAGGGAGGAGAUGAGUGUGGGGCAGGUAAGACAGUGAGCAGAGGUGGUGUUUUCAACGUCUUGGCCUGUAGUUUUCCUGAAUGGCAAUGAAGCAUUUUAUCAGAUUUUCGCAGCCAGGCCUGUGCCAGCAGCCUCAGGGUUGGGAACCAGAUGAGAUGAUGGACACAUUUGGACAGAACCUCUUACCUUAUUCUUUGGGGAAAUUUGUCAAAAGCCAGUUAUCUUUGCAAAACCAAUUUUCAGGGAUUUCACAGAAAUCAUUUCACAAUUUUUGGGUGUUGACAGCUCUGCCAUUAAUCAGCUAGGGUGACCUUGGGAAAGUCACUCUAGGUCCUGCUUUAGAAUUGCUUUUUUUGUUGUUUUGAAAGCAGCUGAUAAAAUCUUGCAGUGGGGUGGGGAGAUCUAGGAACACUUGUCUUGGUUGGUGUUGGCCACUCCCUCCCUCCCCCGUCCCUUGUGUUUUUGCUCCUGCCUCCCUUACAGACCACUUAUAAAUGAGGGGAAAUGCUAAGCAGAACAAUUCUUUCUCAUCCCCUCUUCUCUCCCUCUCUUCUCCUGCUUCCCAGUUUGGGAAUGUAUUAAUAUGUUGGUGUUAGCCCAGAAUUUAAACUCCCAAUUCUACCACCAUGUGUCCAUGAGAAAGUCCAUUUUUAAAUUAACUGAAUCUGCACAUAUUAAUUGAGUACCUACUACAUGCCAAGCACUAUUCCAGGCACUGAGGACACAAAACAGCAGGGACAAAACGGACAAAAGUCUCUGUCCUCAUGAAGCUUAUAUUUUAGUAGGUGGAGACAGAAAAUCAGUCAGUAAAUGAACAGUAAAGUGUUAGCUAAUGAUAAGUACGGUGGAGAAAAAUAAAAUAGGAAAGGAGCUGGAGUGUGUUGGAGGAGGCUGGGGCUUGCAAUUUUAAAUAAGAUGGUUGAGAAACUCGUGGAGAAAGUGAUAUUUAAGCAAAAAAAACUUGAAAGAGGGGAGGGAGUGAGCUAUGUGGGUAUCUCUGGGGAGGGUUAUCCAGGCAGCAGAAACAGCAUGUACAAAGGCUCUGUGGUACAUGUGUUAGAACCCAAGAGCAAGGGAGAGAGGAGCAGGGCCUGAGACCAGAGCGAAACCGGGCACAGAGGUUAGCCGAUCAAGGAUGAUGUUUGGCUUUUUCUCUGAGUGAGACGGGGAGUCACUACAGACUUUUGAGAAGAAGGGUGGCAUGAUUUGCCUAGGUUUUAAAAGGAUCACUUUAACUGCAAUCUUGAAAAUAGACCGUAGAGGGGCCAGGGCAGAAGUAAGGAGGCCAGCUAGGAAGGAGGCUAUUUCAAUUAAGGUAAGAGAUGCUGGUGGCUUGGCUCGGGAUGGCAGCAGUGAAGAUGGUGAGAAGUAGUUGGAUGCUGGAUUUAUUUUGAAAGUGAAGCCAACAUAAUUUGCUGUAAAGGAUAAGAAAAGAGUCAAGGAUAACUCCAUGGUUUUGGGCCCAAGUGACUGGAAGGAUGGAGGGGCCAUUCACCAAGAUGGGCAAGACUGUGGGUUGGGGAGUGGCCAGCAGGGGCUCAGAUUUGGACAUGCUAUGGUUGAGAUGCCCAUCGGACAUCCAUGAGGAGGUUCUGUGUGGACAGAGGUCAAGCAUACAGAUUUUUAAAAUAGCCAUGAUGUAGCAUGAAAUCCCCUGGCGAAGGAGGGUGGCUACUGAAGAGAAGAGGUCCCAGCACCAAGCCCUUGGGCACUGUAAUGCUUAGAAACCAAGGCUCAGUUUCUGCUUCUGUAAAGUAGGGAUAAAAGCCAUAACCACCUCGUGAGCAUUGUCAUGGAGAUUAGUGAGACAGUCCAUGUAAUAAAGUGCAUACAGUAAGAGUACCAAAAACAUGAGUUUCUAUUAAUGACAGAAAUUAUUGUUUCAACAAGCAUGAUGCUGUCUACUUAUAAGUGCUUUUCAACUUUUGAAUCUGUUUUCUAUUAUUUUUGACCGUCAAAACUGUCCUGAGCAAUAAGGCAGGACAUAAUCCUUCCCAUCUGACAAGUGAGAACCCUGAGUUCAGAGAGUGUAAGGGAAGUGCCCAGAUCUCCACCACAUGUUGGUGACAGAGCCAGGGCUGUCAUGGAAACCCCAGACUCCUGCUCCUCUGAUCUCUCUGCCACAGCCUGUAAAUGCUGACAAAUGACUUAAUUAAAGUAGUGCAGGUGCUGUUUGCCAGCAGUAAUGUGGACGCUGACUUCGCUCAGGAUAGCCCAAUGGCACUGCCCACUACAGGUGGUACCAGGGGCCCGGGUUCAUGCUAAAAAUGGCCAGGGAACACAGGCUGCAACCUACAGAGGUGGUGACAGGGCAGAGAGACUUCCUUUUGUCAGACAGUUUCCUUUUGGAAGGCAGAUGAGCAGGUAGAGCUCAUUCCCUACCAGCUCCCUUCAGCAAAGCCUGUGUCUCUGGAGCCUGCUCAGCCCAGAUGCUGCUUUUCUCAGUAGUCAGUGUAACAUGGAACACAGCAGGGAGCAAACUCUGGAGGAAGCUAUGAACCCAGAGCUGGCAGCAUGGGGACAGGCAAGGUCUGGAUUUGUGGGAAGCAGAAUGUCAGUUUUGAAUCAGACGGAGCUAGGUUCAAAUCUCAGCUUCCUUUAUCCCGAGCUGGGAGACCUGGUGCAAGUCAUUUCACCCCUCUGAGCUUUGGCUUUCUCUUCUGCAAGAUGGGAGGGUAAUCCUUGCUUCUCAGCAUUGUUUAAGGAUUAGACAUAACAAUGUAGAGUGAGGGCACAAACAAGGCCUGCUAAAUAGUAGAUAUUAUUAUUAGCAUUAGCAUUAGCAUAUUAGCAAAAGACUUCCAGGGUGAAAUCAAACUACAUUCAACCAAAGCCCUUCUCCUUCACUAACCAUAUCUACCAUUCUCGACUAUCAACAAAUGAUCAGUCAAGAAGCAUUCAUUAGAGCCGACUACACAUAAGGCUUUGUUGUUGAUACAACUAAUACCUCCAUGUGCCCCUGUGCACCAGGAGUGGGCCUUGAGGCUGGGAUGGAACUGGACUCUGCCAGAAUAACUCUGGGCAGCUGGGGCCUGCUCAGGCAGCUACCACCUUUGCCCAGACACCCCUUCCUGUACUGCCCUACCAGCUGGCCCUUUAGAGGCUUGACUGGCAUGGGGGCUCAGGCUCUUGCUGUGGGGUUUACUGCUGCUGAGGCCGGGUGAGCAGCCUGGGCACUGUCCCAAGGCAGGGAACGAGGAGGCAACAUUCCCUGCACGGGAAGGGAACCUUCCUAUAUGGCAGUGCACGCUCACUGUCUUGUCAACUUCCUCACACCUGUGCUGCUGCAAGGAGGGACUGCUCUCCCAUUUUACGAGGCUCAGAGGGGUGAAGUGACAUGCCCAAGACCACGCAGCUGUUUCCAGGCUAGUCUGAUGCUUGGGCUCUGCUCUUUUUCUUCUGCCUGCUUUCUCCCUCCCCAGGCCUUGCUCAGAGGAGGCUGUAGUCACACCAUGGUUGCUGGCCUGCAGUACAGGCUUCAGGGUGGCUCUGGGAAGGGGGUGGCAGUGGGGCUGAGACCGCAUGACAGGAAAAGGUGUCAGGAGCCCUAUACCUGGAUGGGAUGGGAAGAGGUGGUGGAAGAUGGGGCAGCUGCAGGGAUGUGGGAACAUUUGCAGAGGGAGUGCAGGGAGACGAAAUGGUUCUCUUUCAUAAGAGAGUCUGUAGAGAAAAAAAUCAAAGCUUCUUGGAACUUAAACCUAAAAAUGCCAGCUGAAUAUGAUGACAACAACAAUAAUAAAAUAUCUAGUAAUGCCAUACAUUGCAGUAAGCACUUUUCAUAUUGUCAAUCUUCCCAGGAAAUCUGCAGAGUAGACCUUAGUUUCUUUUGCACUUGAUGGCUCAGAGGGGUCACAUAACUUUCCCAAGGUCACCCAACUAAUAAGUGACAGAGCCAGGAUCCAAACCUGGGUCUGUCUCAUUCCAAAACCUUACUCAUUCUGCCAUACCGAGGUGUAAUGCAUCACAGUGUUUGAGCUUAGGUGACAUAGAGGAGGCCCAGAGAGGUUAAGCUGGGCUUGAGACCCAUGGUGGAUUAGUCACAGCCAGUGAAGCUUCCGGUUCUCCAGAGCCACCUUCCCACCCUGCGGCGCUGCAGAAGGGCCAUGCCGGCUGCCAAGGCUCAGCUGUGCUUCUCUCCCAUCAUCCCACAUGCAUAUUAAUCACACACAUAGACUCUAAUGAGCAGUUCAACCUCUGCAGCAGGCUCAGACCAGAAGCCAGGGGUCCUCACCAGCUGGGCAUGAAGAGCCCUGUGCCCACUCCUCCAGCCCUCCAGAGCCUGAGCCGUGCCUUGCUGAACUCCAGCCUGAGCCAUGCCUUGGCCCCCUCUUCUAA